ACAGAUGCCAAACGAGAUGGAGAGAGGGUGAGUAGGAGCAAAAUUUCUCAUGAGAUCUCCCUUCUAAGGCAAUUUGGGUCUCUGCCAAACUUUGGCUAAUAAAAAGAGUCUACAGACUCCUCCGAACACAGAGCUGCAGCUCUUCAGGGAAGAAAUCAAAACAAGAUCACAAGAACUGGGAUGUAACUGCCUUAAAUACUACAAUUGCUGACUACAGGAAACCUCAUCAUCUGAGACCAGCACUUUAUAAAUUAGAAUACUGAAAAAUGAAGCCUAAAAUGAAGUAUUCAACCAACAAAAUUUCCACAGCAAAGUGGAAGAACACAGCAAGCAAAGCCUUGUGUUUCAAGCUGGGAAAAUCCCAACAGAAGGCCAAAGAAGUUUGCCCCAUGUACUUUAUGAAGCUCCGCUCUGGCCUUAUGAUAAAAAAGGAGGCCUGUUACUUUAGGAGAGAAACCACCAAAAGGCCUUCACUGAAAACAGGUAGAAAGCACAAAAGACAUCUGGUACUCGCUGCCUGUCAACAGCAGUCUACUGUGGAGUGCUUUGCCUUUGGUAUAUCAGGGGUCCAGAAAUAUACUAGAGCACUUCAUGAUUCAAGUAUCACAGGAAUUUCACCUAUUACAGAGUAUCUUGCUUCUCUAAGCACAUACAAUGAUCAAUCCAUUACUUUUGCUUUGGAGGAUGAAAGUUAUGAGAUAUAUGUUGAAGACUUGAAAAAAGAUGAAAAGAAAGAUAAGGUGUUACUGAGUUACUAUGAGUCUCAACACCCCUCAAAUGAAUCAGGUGACGGUGUUGAUGGUAAGAUGUUAAUGGUAACCCUGAGUCCUACAAAAGACUUCUGGUUGCAUGCCAACAACAAGGAACACUCUGUGGAGCUCCAUAAGUGUGAAAAACCACUGCCAGACCAGGCCUUCUUUGUCCUUCAUAAUAUGCACUCCAACUGUGUUUCAUUUGAAUGCAAGACUGAUCCUGGAGUGUUUAUAGGUGUAAAGGAUAAUCAUCUUGCUCUGAUUAAAGUAGACUCUUCUGAGAAUUUGUGUACUGAAAAUAUCUUGUUUAAGCUCUCUGAAACUUAGUUGAUGGAAACCUGUGAGUCUUGGGUUGAGUACCCAAAUGCUACCACUGGAGAAGGAAUGAGAGAUAAAGAAAGAGACAGGUGACAUCUAAGGGAAAUGAAGAGUGCUUAGCAUGUGUGGAAUGUUUUCCAUAUUAUGUAUAAAAAUAUUUUUUCUAAUCCUCCAGUUAUUCUUUUAUUUCCCUCUGUAUAACUGCAUCUUCAAUACAAGUAUCAGUAUAUUAAAUAGGGUAUUGGUAAAGAAACGGUCAACAUUCUAAAGAGAUACAGUCUGACCUUUACUUUUCUCUAGUUUCAGUCCAGAAAGAACUUCAUAUUUAGAGCUAAGGCCACUGAGGAAAGAGCCAUAGCUUAAGUCUCUAUGUAGACAGGGAUCCAUUUUAAAGAGCUACUUAGAGAAAUAAUUUUCCACAGUUCCAAACGAUAGGCUCAAACACUAGAGCUGCUAGUAAAAAGAAGACCAGAUGCUUCACAGAAUUAUCAUUUUUUCAACUGGAAUAAAACACCAGGUUUGUUUGUAGAUGUCUUAGGCAACACUCAGAGCAGAUCUCCCUUACUGUCAGGGGAUAUGGAACUUCAAAGGCCCACAUGGCAAGCCAGGUAACAUAAAUGUGUGAAAAAGUAAAGAUAACUAAAAAAUUUAGAAAAAUAAAUCCAGUAUUUGUAAAGUGAAUAACUUCAUUUCUAAUUGUUUAAUUUUUAAAAUUCUGAUUUUUAUAUAUUGAGUUUAAGCAAGGCAUUCUUACACGAGGAAGUGAAGUAAAUUUUAGUUCAGACAUAAAAUUUCACUUAUUAGGAAUAUGUAACAUGCUAAAACUUUUUUUUUUUUAAAGAGUACUGAGUCACAACAUGUUUUAGAGCAUCCAAGUACCAUAUAAUCCAACUAUCAUGGUAAGGCCAGAAAUCUUCUAACCUACCAGAGCCUAGAUGAGACACCGAAUUAACAUUAAAAUUUCAGUAACUGACUGUCCCUCAUGUCCAUGGCCUACCAUCCCUUCUGACCCUGGCUUCCAGGGACCUAUGUCUUUUAAUACUCACUGUCACAUUGGGCAAAGUUGCUUCUAAUCCUUAUUUCCCAUGUGCACAAGUCUUUUUGUAUUCCAGCUUCCUGAUAACACUGCUUACUGUGGAAUAUUCAUUUGACAUCUGUCUCUUUUCAUUUCUUUUAACUACCAUGCCCUUGAUAUAUCUUUUGCACCUGCUGAACUUCAUUUCUGUAUCACCUGACCUCUGGAUGCCAAAACGUUUAUUCUGCUUUGUCUGUUGUAGAAUUUUAGAUAAAGCUAUUAAUGGCAAUAUUUUUUUGCUAAACGUUUUUGUUUUUUACUGUCACUAGGGCAAUAAAAUUUAUACUCAACCAUAUAAUAACAUUUUUUAACUACUAAAGGAGUAGUUUUUAUUUUAAAGUCUUAGCAAUUUCUAUUACAACUUUUCUUAGACUUAACACUUAUGAUAAAUGACUAACAUAGUAACAGAAUCUUUAUGAAAUAUGACCUUUUCUGAAAAUACAUACUUUUACAUUUCUACUUUAUUGAGACCUAUUAGAUGUAAGUGCUAGUAGAAUAUAAGAUAAAAGAGGCUGAGAAUUACCAUACAAGGGUAUUACAACUGUAAAACAAUUUAUCUUUGUUUCAUUGUUCUGUCAAUAAUUGUUACCAAAGAGAUAAAAAUAAAAGCAGAAUGUAUAUCAUCCCAUCUGAAAAACACUAAUUAUUGACAUGUGCAUCUGUACAAUAAACUUAAAAUGAUUAUUAAAUAAUCAAAUAUAUCUACUACAUUGUUUAUAUUAUUGAAUAAAGUAUAUUUUCCAAAUGUA